AGUUGUCUGAGCGAGCGCGAGCCGGGAGCCGGGGCGGGCGCGGGCAGCGGCGGGCCGGCCGGGCUGUGCGGGGCGAGCGGCGGCGGCGGCGGGGGCGCUUCGGCCGGGGCGGCAGCUGGGCGCCGGCGGGAGCUAGCAGCGUCUGCAGCCGCGCCGGCCGCCAGCGCCCCGGCGCGCUCCGGCUCGGCCAUGGAGCUGCCAGCUGUUGGCGAGCACGUCUUCGCGGUGGAGAGCAUCGAGAAGAAGCGGAUCCGCAAGGGCAGAGUGGAGUAUCUGGUGAAAUGGAGAGGCUGGUCGCCCAAAUAUAACACGUGGGAACCGGAGGAGAACAUCCUGGACCCCAGGCUGCUGAUCGCCUUCCAGAACAGGGAACGGCAGGAGCAGCUGAUGGGAUAUCGGAAGAGAGGGCCGAAGCCCAAACCGCUAGUGGUGCAGGUGCCUACCUUUGCCCGUCGUUCCAAUGUCCUGACCGGCCUCCAGGACUCCUCCACUGACAACCGUGCCAAGCUGGAUUUGGGCGCGCAGGGGAAGGGCCAGGGGCAUCAGUACGAGCUCAACAGCAAGAAGCACCACCAGUACCAGCCGCACAGCAAGGAGCGGGCGGGCAAGCCCCCGCCGCCGGGCAAGAGCGGCAAGUACUACUACCAGCUCAACAGCAAGAAGCACCACCCCUACCAGCCCGACCCCAAAAUGUACGACCUGCAGUACCAGGGCGGCCACAAGGAGGCGCCCAGCCCCACCUGCCCGGACCUGGGGGCCAAGAGCCACCCGCCCGACAAGUGGGCGCAAGGUGCGGGGGCCAAAGGCUACCUGGGGGCGGUGAAGCCCCUGGCCGGUGCGGCGGGUGCUCCAGGCAAAGGCUCCGAGAAGGGCCCCCCCAACGGAAUGAUGCCGGCCCCCAAAGAGGCUGUGACGGGCAACGGGAUUGGGGGCAAGAUGAAGAUAGUCAAGAACAAGAACAAGAACGGACGCAUCGUGAUCGUGAUGAGCAAAUACAUGGAGAACGGCAUGCAGGCGGUGAAGAUCAAGUCCGGCGAGGUGGCAGAGGGGGAGGCUCGCUCCCCCAGCCACAAGAAGCGGGCAGCCGACGAGCGCCACCCUCCUGCCGACAGGACUUUUAAAAAGGCGGCGGGCGCAGAGGAGAAGAAGGUGGAGGCGCCGCCCAAGAGGAGGGAGGAGGAGGUGUCCGGGGUUAGCGAUCCGCAGCCCCAGGAUGCCGGCUCCCGCAAGCUGUCCCCGACCAAGGAGGCCUUUGGAGAGCAGCCCCUGCAGCUCACCACCAAGCCCGACCUGCUUGCCUGGGACCCGGCCCGGAACACGCACCCGCCCUCACACCACCCGCACCCGCACCCCCAUCACCACCACCACCACCACCACCACCACCACCACGCCGUCGGCCUGAAUCUCUCCCACGUGCGCAAGCGCUGCCUCUCCGAGACCCACGGCGAGCGCGAGCCCUGCAAGAAGCGGCUGACUGCGCGCAGCAUCAGCACCCCCACCUGCCUGGGGGGCAGCCCAGCCGCUGAGCGCCCGGCCGACCUGCCACCAGCCGCCGCCCUCCCGCAGCCCGAGGUCAUCCUGCUAGACUCAGACCUGGAUGAACCCAUAGACUUGCGCUGCGUCAAGACGCGCAGCGAGGCCGGGGAGCCGCCCAGCUCCCUCCAGGUGAAGCCCGAGACACCGGCGUCGGCGGCGGUGGCGGUGGCGGCGGCAGCGGCACCCACCACGACGGCGGAGAAGCCUCCAGCCGAGGCCCAGGACGAACCUGCAGAGUCGCUGAGCGAGUUCAAGCCCUUCUUUGGGAAUAUAAUUAUCACCGACGUCACCGCGAACUGCCUCACCGUUACUUUCAAGGAGUACGUGACGGUGUAGCCGGAGGGCGUCGGAAGGGGAAGCGCCAUUCCCGCGGGGGGGCGGGGAGCUGAGCACCUGGGGCCUCGGGGCGGGCUCCCCUCUCGCCAACCCGCCAACCGCGAGAGACCCAGGCUGGCCCCCAGGGUGAGGACGCCCGGAGCGGAGGUAACCAUGUUCCCCCUGCGGCGGCUGUCAGACCUGGGCGGAGGCCCCUUCCACGCGGUGCCGGCGGGGCUCGCCCUCUCCUGCCCUUCCCCGCUGGAGAUGGACCCCCGGAACGGACAGGGCAGCUCUGCGCCCGGCCUCAGAGUUCUAGUAUUAUAUUUUAACCGUGCUAACUUGUCAAGUGCUGACUCUACUCCCGUUUGUACGUGGUGUUAUUAUUGAAAUGUAUUGUUUGAGCUCAAAAGGCCCGACCACCCCCCUUCGGGCUGCUAUAUAUAUAUUUAUUUGUAGGUAUUUAUAUAUUGAAAUAUAAAAACCUAGAUUUAUGGAGUUUCCUCUAGAUCAUGUUAUAUUCUAUAUCAGACAAACUAUUUUCUUUUGACCUUUCUUCCCCUCCAUCCAGUAUUUCGGUUGAUUUCAUUUUCUCCCCUCUCUUCCCCUUCCACGAACUGCAAUACCAGUAACCUUGGUAUAUAUUUUUUGAUACUGUACACAUGGAUGUCUUGUUUCUAUGUGCAAAAAAAAAAAAAAAAAAAAGUUUGUUAAAAGGCUACACGAGCUCUCUAGAAACUGCUGCUACUAGAAAUGUCUAAACUAUAAGCUUCCAACUAUUACCUGCUUGAAUGUAAAUAUUAAAUGGAGAUGUUGAAGGUGCA